GGAGCUGGGCCGGGCCCGAGCGGAUCGCGGGCUCGGGCUGCGGGGCUCCGGCUGCGGGCGCUGGGCCGCGAGGCGCGGAGCUUGGGAGCGGAGCCCAGGCCGUGCCGCGCGGCGCCAUGAAGGGCAAGGAGGAGAAGGAGGGCGGCGCACGGCUGGGCGCUGGCGGCGGAAGCCCCGAGAAGAGCCCGAGCGCGCAGGAGCUCAAGGAGCAGGGCAAUCGUCUGUUCGUGGGCCGAAAGUACCCGGAGGCGGCGGCCUGCUACGGCCGCGCGAUCCCAGAGCGCAGAAGCUGGGACGGGCCGUGGGUCAGAGUGGGCACGCUGAGCCUACGCCCUCAUGCGGCUGGCCCGGCCUUGGUCCCUAGACCCGGAACCCGCUGGUGGCCGUGUAUUACACCAACCGGGCCUUGUGCUACCUGAAGAUGCAGCAGCACGAGCAGGCCCUGGCCGACUGCCGGCGCGCCCUGGAGCUGGACGGGCAGUCUGUGAAGGCGCACUUCUUCCUGGGGCAGUGCCAGCUGGAGAUGGAGAGCUAUGAUGAGGCCAUCGCCAAUCUGCAGCGAGCUUACAGCCUGGCCAAGGAGCAGCGGCUGAACUUCGGGGACGACAUCCCCAGCGCUCUUCGAAUCGCGAAGAAGAAGCGCUGGAACAGCAUUGAGGAGCGGCGCAUCCACCAGGAGAGCGAGCUGCACUCCUACCUCUCCAGGCUCAUUGCCGCGGAGCGUGAGAGGGAGCUGGAAGAGUGCCAGCGAAACCACGAGGGUGAUGAGGACGACAGCCACGUCCGGGCCCAGCAGGCCUGCAUUGAGGCCAAGCACGACAAGUACAUGGCGGACAUGGACGAGCUUUUUUCUCAGGUGGAUGAGAAGAGGAAGAAGCGAGACAUCCCCGACUACCUGUGUGGCAAGAUCAGCUUUGAGCUGAUGCGGGAGCCGUGCAUCACGCCCAGUGGCAUCACCUACGACCGCAAGGACAUCGAGGAGCACCUGCAGCGUGUGGGUCAUUUUGACCCCGUGACCCGGAGCCCCCUGACCCAGGAACAGCUCAUCCCCAACUUGGCUAUGAAGGAGGUUAUUGACGCAUUCAUCUCUGAGAAUGGCUGGGUGGAGGACUACUGAGGUUCCCUGCCCUACCUGGCGUCCUGGUCCAGGGGAGCCCUGGGCAGAAGCCCCCGGCCCCUAUACAUAGUUUAUGUUCCUGGCCACCCCGACCGCUUCCCCCAAGUUCUGCUGUUGGACUCUGGACUGUUUCCCCUCUCAGCAUCGCUUUUGCUGGGCCGUGAUCGUCCCCCUUUGUGGGCUGGAAAAGCAGGUGAGGGUGGGCUGGGCUGAGGCCAUUGCCGCCACUAUCUGUGUAAUAAAAUCCGUGAGCACGAGGUGGGACGUGCUGGUGUGUGACCGGCAGUCCUGCCAGCUGUUUUGGCUAGCCGA